GCCCCGCAGCCCUGCCGGACACCCCGGGCUGCAGCUGAGCGGGCGCAGACGGGCCGAGGCGGGCGCCGGGCGCGCAGGGACCGAGGGACCGAGUGCUCCCCAUGAGCGCACGUGGGCCGGGCGGUCCGCAAGCCCGGCUGAGAGCGCGCCAUGGGGCAGGCGGGCUGCAAGGGGCUCUGCCUGUCGCUGUUCGACUACAAGACCGAGAAGUAUGUCAUCGCCAAGAACAAGAAGGUGGGCCUGCUGUACCGGCUGCUGCAGGCCUCCAUCCUGGCGUACCUGGUCGUAUGGGUGUUCCUGAUAAAGAAGGGUUACCAAGACGUCGACACCUCCCUGCAGAGUGCUGUCAUCACCAAAGUCAAGGGCGUGGCCUUCACCAACACCUCGGAUCUUGGGCAGCGGAUCUGGGAUGUCGCCGACUACGUCAUUCCAGCCCAGGGAGAGAACGUCUUUUUUGUGGUCACCAACCUGAUUGUGACCCCCAACCAGCGGCAGAACGUCUGUGCUGAGAAUGAAGGCAUUCCUGAUGGCGCGUGCUCCAAGGACAGCGACUGCCACGCUGGGGAAGCGGUUACAGCUGGAAACGGAGUGAAGACCGGCCGCUGCCUGCGGAGAGAGAACUUGGCCAGGGGCACCUGUGAGAUCUUUGCCUGGUGCCCGUUGGAGACAAGCUCCAGGCCGGAGGAGCCAUUCCUGAAGGAGGCCGAAGACUUCACCAUUUUCAUAAAGAACCACAUCCGUUUCCCCAAAUUCAACUUCUCCAAAAGCAAUGUGAUGGACGUCAAGGACAGAUCUUUCCUGAAAUCAUGCCACUUUGGCCCCAAGAACCACUACUGCCCCAUCUUCCGACUGGGCUCCGUGAUCCGCUGGGCCGGGAGCGACUUCCAGGAUAUAGCCCUGGAGGGUGGCGUGAUAGGAAUUAAUAUUGAAUGGAACUGUGAUCUUGAUAAAGCUGCCUCUGAGUGCCACCCUCACUAUUCUUUUAGCCGUCUGGACAAUAAACUUUCAAAGUCUGUCUCCUCCGGGUACAACUUCAGAUUUGCCAGAUAUUACCGAGACGCAGCCGGGGUGGAGUUCCGCACCCUGAUGAAAGCCUACGGGAUCCGCUUUGACGUGAUGGUGAACGGCAAGGGUGCUUUCUUCUGCGACCUGGUACUCAUCUACCUCAUCAAAAAGAGAGAGUUUUACCGUGACAAGAAGUACGAGGAAGUGAGGGGCCUAGAAGACAGUUCCCAGGAGGCCGAGGACGAGGCAUCGGGGCUGGGGCUAUCUGAGCAGCUCACAUCUGGGCCAGGGCUGCUGGGGAUGCCGGAGCAGCAGGAGCUGCAGGAGCCACCCGAGGCGAAGCGUGGAAGCAGCAGUCAGAAGGGGAACGGAUCUGUGUGCCCACAGCUCCUGGAGCCCCACAGGAGCACGUGAAUUGCCUCUGCUUACGUUCAGGCCCUGUCCUAAACCCAGCCGUCUAGCACCCAGUGAUCCCAUGCCUUUGGGAAUCCCAGGAUGCUGCCCAACGGGAAAUUUGUACAUUGGGUGCUAUCAAUGCCACAUCACAGGGACCAGCCAUCACAGAGCAAAGUGACCUCCACGUCUGAUGCUGGGGUCAUCAGGACGGACCCAUCAUGGCUGUCUUUUUGCCCCACCCCCUGCCGUCAGUUCUUCCUUUCUCCGUGGCUGGCUUCCCGCACUAGGGAACGGGUUGUAAAUGGGGAACAUGACUUCCUUCCGGAGUCCUUGAGCACCUCAGCUAAGGACCGCAGUGCCCUGUAGAGUUCCUAGAUUACCUCACUGGGAAUAGCAUUGUGCGUGUCCGGAAAAGGGCUCCAUUUGGUUCCAGCCCACUCCCCUCUGCAAGUGCCGCAGCUUCCCUCAGAGCAUACUCUCCAGUGGAUCCAAGUACUCUCUCUCCUAAAGACACCACCUUCCUGCCAGCUGUUUGCCCUUAGGCCAGUACACAGAAUUAAAGUGGGGGAGAUGGCAGACGCUUUCUGGGACCUGCCCAAGAUAUGUAUUCUCUGACACUCUUAUUUGGUCAUAAAACAAUAAAUGGUGUCAAUUUCAAA